GAGAAGGCCCAGGAAGUGACGGCCGCCUCCCGGCUACCGGGGACUUCUGGAGUCCGAGAAGUCAACGGCGCGGUUGCUGCGGCCGCCGCGCUCCCCGGCCCGAGGCGAUGGAGAACGGAGCGGUGUACAGCCCCACUACGGAGGAGGACCCGGGCCCCGCCAGAGGCCCCCGGAGCGGCCUCGCUGCCUACUUUUUCAUGGGCCGGCUCCCAUUGCUCCGGCGCGUUCUCAAGGGCUUGCAGCUGUUGCUGUCUCUGCUGGCCUUCAUCUGUGAAGAAGUUGUAUCACAAUGUACUUUAUGUGGAGGACUUUAUUUUUUUGAGUUUGUAAGCUGCAGUGCCUUUCUUCUGAGUCUCCUUAUACUGAUUGUGUAUUGCACUCCAUUUUAUGAGAGAGUUGAUACCACAAAAGUAAAAUCAUCGGAUUUUUAUAUUACUUUGGGAACAGGAUGUGUGUUUUUGUUGGCAUCCAUCAUUUUUGUUUCCACACAUGACAGGACUUCAGCUGAGAUUGCUGCAAUUGUGUUUGGAUUUAUAGCAAGUUUUAUGUUCCUACUUGACUUUAUCACUAUGCUGUAUGAAAAACGACAGGAGUCCCAGCUGAGAAAACCUGAAAAUACCACUAGGGCUGAAGCCCUCACUGAGCCACUUAAUGCCUAAAGACUCUGGGGAGCAGAUGUUACCUAAGGUAGUGACCCUGCAUUGUGGUGCCUGAGCCCUGGCAGAAGCUCUUGUAAAAUUUGUUAAUUGUUUAAACCACUUCUUUUGGAGAGCAAGGGGAAGGUCAAGAAGGCAGUUUUAUCAAUAUUGUGUCAGUCACCACAAAGUAGGCCAGAUAAGUUAAAAAAAAUUUUUUUUUAAAUAAUAAUUGAAACUUAUCUCAAAUGGAGAUUUUGGUGGGAGGAGGAGAAAACAAUUGUUUUUAAAUCACACAGCUCAACGGUUGAUAAAUGAUUCUGUCAUUCUGUUACAGGUCAUUCUUUUACUAGGCUUAGCUUCCAAAUUAUGCUUUAUAGCUGUAUAAACAUCGUGAUUAUAUUCAUCUACUUAGAAAUUGUUUUAUUUUUAAAUUAAUUUGCUUAGCUGUUUGUUUUGAUGCUUAGAUUAUGUUCUGUUAAUGGGAAUUUAACAUAUUUAAGAAACCAAUAUUUAAAAUGUUGGUCUAGGUUUUUUUCCUUAACAUAUAUUACCAGGCUUUACUGUAUUUCACUCAGCCUUAAAUGUUAUAAUAUUUUUGGAUAACGGUUAUUAAUUCUUUGAGACCUUCGUAUAGCCUAUAAAAUGUAUGGGAGAUGUUGGUAUUUUAUGUGUAUAAAAGCAACAAUAUCAGCAACUUCGUGUUUAUACUGCACCUUGGUUGUUGAUGUCAAGUAAAAAAAAGAUUGUUUUGUAACACAUAAAAAAAUGGAAGAAACUGAUACCACACCUAAGGACCAAAGAUAAGAAAGACUUUUUGCCCAAGACAGUGAAAGUAAUUAUAAAAACAAGCUUUGACCACUUACCAAGUAUCUGAAGAGAUGAGUUCAUACUAUGAUUUAGAAAGUGGUUCAAUUCCCCUGUUGGCAUAUGAUUAUUUUUACUAAAAUUAAUACAGCUCUGUGGGUCUUCCUUAGUGUUUUCUUUGAAGCCAAUCUGUUUUUUUUAGGACACCAGCCUUUGGUUUUUCAUCUGUUCGAGAUGCCUCUUCUCUGUCUCCUUAUCAGAUAGAAAUGGAGUCAUGUGCUGCUGCUUCAUCUAGCAGAGGUUGGCCUCUGGCUCUGACACUUUUUGUCAGUUGUCUUUAGGUGGUCCUGAAUCUUGGGCCCUUUUGAUUGUGAAUACUGUGUAGCAGGAUCUUGAGAGUCCUUGUUCUUACAUAGGCAUUGCUCUAGUUUGUCUUUGGCAAAAAAAAAAAAAAAAAAAAGUAAAUAUCCAGGGAACCCUGCCCAGACUAAUACUGUUGGUGGCAUAAGAGAAUCAAGCCAUUCUCAAGAGAUAACUUCAUAACCAGAAUUGUCUGUUGGCUAGCAGCUGUCACAGAUAGGCAGGGCACUUGGGAUAUGACCUUUCUGUCCAGGUGAUUCACAGACUAGACCUUUCUUAUCCUCCUCCUAGAGUUUUGACUUGGGACUCUAGUGUUAAGAUGAUGAGCCCGUGCAUCAGGUCCUUCUGCACUUUGGUGGAAGUCUCCCAGGGUAGGUUUCCUAUUUGAAACAGUGGAAUCAUGUUUCCAGUGAUAAAGUUUAAUGACCUCAUCCUUUUUUUUUUUUCUCAUCUGCCAUUUGUGUGUCUUAGAUGGGUUUUAAUUGCAUGAAUGUGGCUAAUGUGGUUCUCAGAAAUUGGUCAGUAUGGCCCAACAUAGCUUCUGCUCUGUCUUACUGACUCAAUACCUUUAGGAUUUGUAUCAGAGUUUGGAUACUAGUGUUAGUGGUGGUGUCACCACUACUUAAUUGGGAGAUAAUGAAACCAAUCAUGGAUGCUGUUUUUAUUGGGCAUGUCAUCUAAGAGAGGAGAAAUAGCUGGGUUUUGGGUCUAAUUAUGAAUAAGGACUGAUUCAGAAAACGAGUUUAUGGUAGGUAGACUAAAGUUUCACAUCAGACUGUACCAUUGUGAUUUAGACCUAUCUAAAAUUCAGAGCAUAUCAUCUGGGCUACCUCAGGGUCACCACCCAUGUAUUGGGCUUAGUCAGGAUUGACAGAUACAUUCUCAGCUGGCCUGUCAUAUAAAACAUACUGUCAUUGAGCUUAAGCUCCGCUUGUUCUGAGGUUUCACCUCCAUGUGUUUCAUUGGUGCAAAAGUGGAUCUCUUAGUUGGUCACUUAAUUCUUUCUUUUUCAGAAAGAUAGUAUGUUCACUGGUAUAUUUGGUCACUCUUAGAACCUUCCUUCACAUUGUUUUUUAUGGGACCCAUGAAUGGUUAGCCUUUCUUUUCUAUUGUAGAAGGAAAUAAAUAGGAGUAAAAAGACCAUUGUAGUAAAUAAGUUCAAGGGGAACUUGGGACCAGAAACCACUGUUAUGUACAAAAAAAUGGCAAAUUCAAUAAACUCAAAUUUAAAAUAAUUUUUAAAUUAACAGUUAUGAUAAAUUUUAUAUUUUAUACAAAUAGAUUGCUUAGAAUGGUUCUCAAGAAUUAUAAGAGAAAUGAACUCACAGUACAAAAAUUUUAUAAUUACUAUACUUGUGUUUUGUUUGGGGGCUGGGAAAUGUAUUUUUACAUUGUAGCCAAUCAUUUUAUAUUUGUCAAUUUAAAUCUUAUGGGUCUUUUUUUUUUAUCUCUCUUGAUGUCAGAUUUUAUAGUCUUUUUAAAUAAAUCCAUUUAAUUAAAACGUU